GUCCGUCCUCACUCACUGUGUUUGAGGAACUGAGGGCCAGCUGGCAGUGGGAUGAGGCUGGCCCCCUCCUCCGCUUUACUUCCUGGAGGCCUUCCGUAGAGCUGUGGGAGCUGGAGCUGGCAUUUCGUUUGAGGCAGGAUCUGGUCCGGGAGGUCUGGGAUCUCUGGUUAUAUCUCACUUCUGACCUCUGGGCACGUGCUGCAGCUGUGGCUGAGGCCAAGAAAUGUGAGGGGCCUCCAUCCACUGCAUUGAGUAGUGACCCCGACGUGGGGUUCAAUGUGGAGGGGGGAGGGGCUGCUGCGGCAGCUGCAGGAGCCGACCUUGUUCUUCUCAUGCCGGCAUCCCUGCUUGCAGCUGUGAAGGGGGCAGGAAUCAUCGAGGUGACCUGGGCUGAGUCCCGGGAGUGGGAAGAGUUGGCAGGAAGGGGAUCUGAGGAGGAGAACAGGGGUCCUGGUGGUCUGUGCUUCUUCCCAGACACGGGAGCUGUAGCGGGGACCUCUGCAGCAGAUGCUAGGGGGGCCACUAGGCCCAGGCAGUCUUGGGACUUGGGUCUGUCCUGCUGUGCAUCCAUAGUGGGUGCUUUAGAAACGGGAGGCCCACCCGAAGCCCCUGUUGCAAGUGAGGACAAAGUGUGGGAAGGCCGUGAGGGUCUGCAGUCCGGGAUGGCCUUGUCCUCAACGUGCAGUGCACUGUUGAUGCGCUGGAAUGCCGUCUCUUUUUCCAGGUGCAGGUCUUCAGCCGUGACCCGGUACCCCAGCUCUAAGGGAGGUGGCAGCAUCAAAGGCUCCCCUCGCCUGCGUGGCAGCAGGGGAAUCUUGCGUCUACGGGGCCUAGAGUCCUGGGAUCUGGGGGAGCCACCCGUUGGGGCGAUUGUCUGCCCUGGUGCUGUAUCUGCCCCCUUUUCACACCGUGUGUGACCCGAAGAGACAGCCUGAGGCCUGUCCUCACUCACUGUCUUUGAGUAACUGAGGGUCAGCUGGCAGCGGGAUGAGGCUGGCCCCCUCCUCUGCUUUAGCCCCGGCAAGCCUCCCGUGGAGCUGUAGGAGCUGGAGAUGGCAUUUCGUUUGGUGCUCGAGCUCGUCCAGGAUGUCUGGGAUGUGUGGUUAUAUCUGAUUUCUGAGCUCUGGGCGUGGAGGUCUGUCUGCAGAGGCCCGGGCCUGGGCACAAAGGGAGAGGGGCCUCCAUUGUCCCGCAGGGGCCAAAAUGCAGACCGUGCAUCCCCGGUGACCUCGGGGACCGUUCUCUGAUCAUCAGGAUUUUCUUGGACUCUGGGGUCCUUGUCCUGCUCAGGCAUCCCUGCCCCGCUCUCCUUGAGGGCCCUCAACACUAUCUUCCCUGGACACAAGUCUGGGGACAGCCGGGUGUUGUGGACCCCAAAGGGGUGACUACCUGCUCCUGGGCCCCACAGAGUCCUUGUGCUCAGUGUAGUGGCUGAGCUGGGGGAUGCCCUGGAACUCGGAGCACACAGCACUGGCUUACUGUGGUACCUGUGCAGUGAAAUUGAAGACAGAAUCACCAGGAUGGAACACAGGUCUUGCAGGAUCACGGAAAACCUUCUUAGAGUUGUCUUGACACCACUGAUGUCGAGUGUGCGGGUGUUUGUAGGAUGGCCUGCCACUCAGUCCAGGGGCAGGAGCAACGGGGAGAUCCCACAAGCAAAGUGAACUGGGGGAUGGGCUGAAGGGGCUCCAGGCAACUGAGCCCUACUCGCAGGUCCUCGGCCUUGGCCCAAACAGGAAUGAGGGGCACAGAGUGCCCGGGUAACCGCUCCUGGGAGCAGUGGGGAACUGUCGGAUACUUGAACUCUCAAGAGCUGGGCUCUGAGCGUCCUCGUCCAGCUGCCAACUUGGCCAAAGGCUAAGCCAGCAGAUUGUUCUGUUGCCGGGCAACGCGACUUCUAAACCUGAGGGAGUGGGCAUGUGAGCACAUAAUGGCACCAGUGACAGAGCGACCAUAAUGGAUGAAUAAGCACAGCCAGGGCUGGUGAAUUACCAGAUCUCCGUCAAGUGCAGUAACCAGUUCAAGUUGGAAGUGUGUCUUUUGAAUGCAGAAAACAAAGUCGUGGACAACCAGGCUGGGACCCAGGGCCAGCUGAAGGUGCUGGGUGCCAACCUCUGGUGGCCGUACCUGAUGCACGAACACCCCGCCU